ACUUGGCCCUCGCUCUCACUCGCGGUCGCCUGGCCGUUGUCAUUGUCCCUCCGCUGUCACCUUUUCAAGCCCCAGGCUGGCUGCUUCAGAAGCCCCUGACCCCAUGGAGGAGUGGGACGUGCCACAGAUGAAGAAAGAGGUGGAGAGCCUCAAGUACCAGCUGGCCUUCCAGCGGGAGAUGGCGUCCAAGACCAUCCCCGAGCUGCUGAAGUGGAUCGAGGACGGGAUCCCCAAGGACCCCUUCCUGAACCCCGACCUGAUGAAGAACAACCCAUGGGUGGAAAAGGGCAAAUGCACCAUCCUGUGAGCCCCGCACCCGGCCCCUCUCACACCAUCCUGUGAGACCACGCCCGGCCCCACUCCCACCAUCUUGUAAGACUGUGCCCAGCCCCACUCACUCCAUCCUGUGAGUCCCACUCCCAGCCCCACUCCCACCAUCCUGUGAGCCCAUGCCCGGCCCCACUCACACCAACCUGUGAGCCCCACUCCCGGCCCCACUCACUCCAUCUUGUAAGACUAUGCCCAGCCCCAUUCACUCCAUCCUGUGAGUCCCACUCCCAGCCCCACUCCCACCAUCCUGUGAGCCCCACUUCCAGCCCCACUCCCACCAUCCUGUGAGCCCCACUCCCAGCCCCACUCCCACCAUCCUGUGAGCCCCACUCCCGGCCCCACUCACUCCAUCCUGUGAGCCCCACUCCCAGCCCCACUCACACCAACCUGUGAGCCCCACUCCCGGCCCCACUCACAACAUCUUGUAAGACUGUGCCCGGCCCCAUUCACUCCAUCCUGUGAGACCACGCCCGGCCCCACUCACUCUAUCCUGUGAGACCACGCCUGGCCCCACUCCCACCAUCCUGUGAGCCCCACUCCUGGCCCCACUCACACCAUCCUAUGAGCCCACGCCCGGCCCCACUCCCACCAUCCUGUGAACCCCACUCCACUCGCACGUGAUUACAGUCUGUAAAGGUGUGACUUUAUAAAGACA